GAGUGCCUCCUGGUCCCUGUCUGCCGGCAUUCGCGGCUGCGGGGCCCGGAGGUGGGACUGGCUUCCCGGUGCCGCGAGGGCGGGUCCGGACAGCCUUCCCCCCAGUCCGGCGCACCAUCUCCCUGCCUUGUGGCUGGAGGCGCCGCGGACCCAAAGGGAGGGACCAUCCCGGGAAGCAGCCCCGAGAGCGGAAGUGCAGAAUGGCUUCCUCGAGAGAGUAAAGUGCAGCCUCUCCAGACACUGGGGCCCCAGUGGGCGUGGGCGAAGGUAAUCCAGGCCUGGGUACGAUUCCGGGCCCUCCUUCGACUUCCCAGCGGUUGCUGGUAGGAGGAGUUGGCGGAAGCACUUGGAACUCCUUUAUAAGUGUCAGCUGUGAGGUAAAAACUGUUGAUGAGAUCUUGUGGGUUUUGUUUUGGGUUCACUAAUUUGGGCGGGGGCUACAUAACUGCCUACUUGAGUUUGCAAUAUGAGAAUGGUAAUAGCGACCCACUUAGCAGAAUUAUGAUGUCACAAAGCUCAAAGGACUGUUUAAUGAAAGGCUCAGAGGAUCAUAUACUGGAAAAUUUUUCCACACACGCUGUAAGCCACAUGCUUUUUUUUUUUUUUUUAAGUCAUGCAUUUAAGUGCUGGAGUGAAGUUGAGGUGCACUAUUAAUGACUCAUAUUCAGAACCUGAAGAGAGAGAUCCCUUUUGUGCUAAAUUUUAAUUUGAUUUGAAAAUGAGUAAGUGCAGAAAGACACCAGUUCAGCAGCUAGCAAGUCCCGCGUCAUUCAGCCCAGAUAUUCUUGCUGACAUUUUUGAACUCUUUGCCAAGAACUUUUCUUAUGGCAAGCCACUUAAUAAUGAGUGGCAGUUACCAGAUCCCAGUGAGAUUUUCACCUGUGACCACACUGAACUUAAUGCAUUUCUUGAUUUGAAGAACUCCCUAAAUGAAGUAAAAAACCUACUGAGUGAUAAGAAACUGGAUGAGUGGCAUGAGCACACUGCUUUCACUAAUAAAGCGGGGAAAAUCAUUUCUCAUGUUAGAAAAUCUGUGAAUGCUGAACUUUGUACUCAAGCAUGGUGUAAGUUCCAUGAGAUUUUGUGCAGCUUUCCACUUAUUCCACAGGAAGCUUUUCAGAAUGGAAAACUGAAUUCUCUACACCUUUGUGAAGCUCCAGGAGCUUUUAUAGCUAGUCUCAACCACUACUUAAAAUCCCAUCGGUUUCCUUGUCAUUGGAGUUGGGUAGCGAAUACUCUGAAUCCAUACCAUGAAGCAAAUGACGACCUCAUGAUGAUUAUGGAUGACCGGCUUAUUGCAAAUACCUUGCACUGGUGGUACUUUGGUCCAGAUAACACUGGUGAUAUCAUGACCCUGAAAUUCUUGACUGGACUUCAGAAUUUCAUAAGCAGCAUGGCUACUGUUCACUUGGUCACUGCAGAUGGGAGUUUUGAUUGCCAAGGAAACCCAGGUGAACAAGAAGCUUUAGUUUCUUCUUUGCAUUACUGUGAAGUUGUCACUGCUCUGACCACUCUUGGAAACGGUGGCUCUUUUGUUCUAAAGAUGUUUACUAUGUUUGAACAUUGUUCCAUAAACUUGAUGUACCUGCUAAACUGUUGUUUUGACCAAGUCCAUGUUUUCAAACCUGCUACUAGCAAGGCAGGAAACUCCGAAGUCUAUGUGGUUUGCCUCCACUAUAAGGGGAGAGAGGCCAUCCAUCCUCUGUUAUCUAAGAUGACCUUGAAUUUUGGGACUGAAAUGAAAAGGAAAGCCCUUUUUCCCCAUCAUGUGAUUCCUGAUUCUUUUCUUAAGAGACAUGAAGAAUGUUGUGUGUUCUUUCAUAAAUAUCAGCUAGAGACUAUUUCUGAAAACAUUCGUCUAUUUGAGUGCAUGGGAAAGGCGGAACAAGAAAAGCUGAAUAAUUUAAGGGAUUGUGCUAUACAAUAUUUUAUGCAAAAAUUUCAACUGAAACAUCUUUCCAGAAAUAAUUGGCUAGUAAAAAAAUCUAGUAUUGGUUGUAGUACAAAUACAAAAUGGUUUGGGCAGAGGAACAAAUAUUUUAAAACUUAUAAUGAAAGGAAGAUGCUAGAAGCCCUUUCAUGGAAAGAUAAAGUAGCCAAAGGAUACUUUAAUAGUUGGGCUGAAGAACAUGGUGUAUAUCAUCCUGGGCAGAGUUCUAUUUUAGAAGGAACAGCUUCCAAUCUUGAGUGUCACUUAUGGCAUAUUUUGGAGGGAAAGAAACUGCCAAAGGUAAAAUGUUCUCCUUUUUGCAAUGGUGAAAUUUUAAAAACUCUUAAUGAAGCAAUUGAAAAGUCAUUAGGAGGAGCUUUUAAUUUGGAUUCCAAGUUUAGGCCAAAACAGCAGUAUUCUUGUUCUUGUCAUGUUUUUUCUGAAGAACUGAUAUUUUCCGAGUUGUGUAGCCUUACUGAGUGCCUUCAGGAUGAGCAGGUUGUAGUACCCAGCAAUCAAAUAAAGUGCCUGCUGGUGGGCUUUUCGACUCUCCGUAAUAUCAAAAUGCAUAUACCGUUGGAAGUUCGACUCCUAGAAUCAGCUGAACUCACAACUUUUAGCUGUUCAUUGCUUCAUGAUGGAGAUCCAACUUACCAGCGUUUAUUUUUGGACUGCCUUCUACAUUCAUUGCGGGAGCUUCAUACAGGAGAUGUUAUGAUUUUGCCUGUACUUUCUUGCUUCACAAGAUUUAUGGCUGGUUUGAUCUUUGUACUCCACAGUUGUUUUAGAUUCAUCACUUUUGUUUGUCCCACAUCCUCUGAUCCCCUGAGGACCUGCGCAGUCCUGCUAUGUGUUGGUUAUCAGGACCUUCCAAAUCCAGUUUUCCGAUAUUUGCAGAGUGUGAAUGAAUUGUUGAGCACUUUGCUCAACUCUGACUCACCCCAGCAGGUUUUACAGUUUGUGCCAAUGGAGGUACUCCUUAAGGGGGCCCUGCUUGAUUUUUUGUGGGAUUUGAAUGCUGCCAUUGCUAAAAGGCAUUUGCAUUUCAUUAUUCAAAGAGAGAGAGAAGAAAUUAUCAACAGCCUUCAGUUACAAAACUGAACAUAUGCUUUCUGAGAUUCAACUUUAUGAUUUCUUAUAAUUUGCCCAGUAUUUGCAUCCUGUUGCUCUAUUAAUUUAAAAACCUUUUAUUUUGGGGAAAGGCCAACAUUUGCAUCAUUCAAAGUCUCAUUAAUUCUGGAAAACCAUCCAUUCUGAUCUCUAGGGUAUAUACACCCACAGGCAUAGAGCUCUUCCACGUGGUGGAAUCUAUGCAAUGAUAGAUAUUCACACUCUAAAUAUGAGGUGUGUGUAUGUGUAUGGGUGGCCACAGCCAUGCUUACCUAUGCCAUUUAGUUGGUCUUACUUAAUCUGCUUAAGAUUUGCAUCUGUGUACCUUUGUUCAGAUUAGUUUUUUUUUUCCAGCCGAUUUCCUCUUAGUGGCUAAUGCUGUUAGUGAAUUUUCCAACUAAUUUCCUCUCAUUGGUUAAUGUUGUUAAUGAAUUGAGAGAGGUAAUUGAGGAAAGGAAAUGAGUAAAUCACUGUUCAGCAACACUGAUUUCCGUUAACACAUCAGUUAUGAAUUUCAGGGAAUUCAUCUCGCCAGAUUCUUGAUAACAUGCCAUUCAUUGCCCUUAGGUGAUUGACCCUAUUUUCUUACAUGGCUCAAAUAAAACUAGUAUGCUGUUGUAUGAAUCUUUUACUGACCACACCAUCCAACUAUAAAAAUAUAACGGGACAGCUUUAAACCAAAGAUCAUGUUUAGAACAAUGAAAAAUUAUUUGUUGUAUCUAAUACACGCCUGUAUUGUGAAAAGCUUCAUUUAGCAAUGAUGUAAUAAUUUUUAACUUCCAGGAAAUAAUCUGUGAAUGGAAAGAUUUUUUAAGAUUUUGAGAUAGUGUUUAGUCUCAUGUUGGGAACACAUGAAUGUGAUGAACAUAGUGAAUACUAAAGAAAACGCUUCAGACUUUCAGAAUGAUGGUUCAGAAUUUAAAAUUUUUAAUCUUUUCUAAUUUCUUUUUUUCAGUGUGAAAAUAGCACUUUACCAAAAGAUUAGCCAUGAAAUGGUUAUUUUGCCAGUUACAUUUGAUUUCUUUUGUAUCUGCAAUGUAAUGAGUUAUUUUAUUUCUUCUGUAUUUGCAGUGUAAUGAGUUUUUGUGGCAAAGUGUAUUAAGCAAUUUUUCAUUAUCUUGAAGUUCCACAAAGUGGAGAAUAUUUAUAUUCUCACAUGCAUUUUAGGCACUUUUGAUAUGUGAAAAUAGAUGUAUUUUCUGAUGCAUUUGGUUAAUAAAUAUUAAUCUGAACAUUUUCAUGUUCUUUGCUAUUUUGAAUUCCAUUAUAGAUUCAUGAAUAAAGUCAUUACUAGAGAGAUUUUGUGUUCAUCUUUUUUAAAUGGAAUUAUGGGAGAAGUUAAAAAUAUAAGUUGGAAACAGACAUUUUUAAAGGGAGUUUUGAAUGAUAGUUAAUGUUCUUUCAUUUUCUCUGAUUUGCAUUCAUUAAAAUUUAGUCCUUAAUAUUGUAAUACUUAUGGAAGGCCUACUUCAGGAAAGAAAUUGAAUACUUAAGGGGGAUUGGAAGAGGAGUGUGUGGAGGCCUGGAAGUAGAUUUUUGAAAGAAAUCUGAUUUCCUACUGGUGACUCUAUGGAAGCAAUUCCAGUUGUAUGACGAUGGAAGUCUGACAGAAGGUUGAUUACCAGGAGGAAAAAAAAAAACACUCUUGGAAAACCAUUUUGCACUUAAUAGUCUUUAUGCCUUGCUAAGUGGGAUUCAAUAUACUAAUAAUGCAGCUUAUUUUUUACUUAUUUUAACUAUUUGAUAAGAAUGAAGUUGAAGGCAUGGGUCCAGAUUCUAGCAUUAUUACUGUCUUUAAGCCCUUCAAAUAAGUAUUGAAUGCUUAGUGUUUUGUUGACACUAAUCUGUACUGGAAUAUAUAACACUGAAGUAUUCUCAAAUGUAUUUUGCUUUUUAACGUGGGUUUUGGAAUCAAUUGCUCAUCUGAUUCAUUGGAUUCAAAUUGCUUUAGAGGUUAGACAUGACUUGAGGAAGGUUCAGAUUGAACUGGAUAUAUUAAUAGAUGACAGGUACUAAUGAUUUAUAUGAGUUUCUCUUUAAGAGAAAGGAGAGGAAAAAUGCUAUUCAAAAGAUGAAUGGAAAAGUAGAAGAAGACAGGAAGAGGUGAGAGUAUGCAUGUUUUACCAAGGUAGACUGUUCUUAAAAACUUUUUUCCACAGGUUUUGAGAUUUUUAAUUUGUAAUAUCUAUUAAAAAACAAACAUCAAA